CCUUUUCCCACCCCCUAGCGCCGCUGGGCCUGCAGGUCUCUGUCGAGCAGCGGACGCCGGUCUCUGUUCCGCAGGAUGGGGUUUGUUAAAGUUGUUAAGAAUAAGGCCUACUUUAAGAGAUACCAAGUGAAAUUUAGAAGACGACGAGAGGGUAAAACUGAUUAUUAUGCUCGGAAACGCUUGGUGAUACAAGAUAAAAAUAAAUACAACACACCCAAAUACAGGAUGAUAGUUCGUGUGACAAACAGAGAUAUCAUUUGUCAGAUUGCUUAUGCCCGUAUAGAGGGGGAUAUGAUAGUCUGCGCAGCGUAUGCACACGAACUGCCAAAAUAUGGUGUGAAGGUUGGCCUGACAAAUUAUGCUGCAGCAUAUUGUACUGGCCUGCUGCUGGCCCGCAGGCUUCUCAAUAGGUUUGGCAUGGACAAGAUCUAUGAAGGCCAAGUGGAGGUGACUGGUGAUGAAUACAAUGUGGAAAGCAUUGAUGGUCAGCCAGGUGCCUUCACCUGCUAUUUGGAUGCAGGCCUUGCCAGAACUACCACUGGCAAUAAAGUUUUUGGUGCCCUGAAGGGAGCUGUGGAUGGAGGCUUGUCUAUCCCUCACAGUACCAAACGAUUCCCUGGUUAUGAUUCUGAAAGCAAGGAAUUUAAUGCAGAAGUACAUCGGAAGCACAUCAUGGGCCAGAAUGUUGCAGAUUACAUGCGCUACUUAAUGGAAGAAGAUGAAGAUGCUUACAAGAAACAGUUCUCUCAAUACAUAAAGAACAGCGUAACUCCAGACAUGAUGGAGGAGAUGUAUAAGAAAGCUCAUGCUGCUAUACGAGAGAAUCCAGUCUAUGAAAAGAAGCCCAAGAAAGAAGUUAAAAAGAAGAGGUGGAACCGUCCCAAAAUGUCCCUUGCUCAGAAGAAGGAUCGGGUAGCUCAAAAGAAGGCAAGCUUCCUCAGAGCUCAGGAGCGGGCUGCUGAGAGCUAAACCCAGCAAUUUUCUAUGAUUUUUUCAGAUAUAGAUAAUAAACUUAUGAACAGCAACUA